GAUGAGACCAGAGGCCGAACUCAGGUUCUGAUGGCCGAGCUGCCCCACAGGAUCAUCAAGGAAACCCAGCGUUUGCUGGCAGAGCCAGUUCCUGGCAUCAAAGCAGAACCAGAUGAAAGCAACGCCCGUUAUUUUCAUGUGGUCAUUGCUGGGGAAUCAAAGGAUUCCCCCUUUGAGGGAGGGACUUUUAAACGUGAACUAUUACUUGCAGAAGAAUACCCAAUGGCAGCCCCUAAAGUACGUUUCAUGACCAAAAUUUAUCAUCCAAAUGUAGACAAGUUGGAAAGAAUAAGUUUAGAUAUUUUGAAAGAUAAGUGGUCCCCAGCCCUGCAGAUCCGCACAGUUCUGCUAUCGAUCCAGGCCUUGUUAAAUGCUCCCAAUCCAGAUGAUCCAUUAGCAAAUGAUGUAGUGGAGCAGUGGAAGACCAACGAAGCCCAAGCCAUUGAAACAGCUAGAGCAUGGACUAGGCUAUAUGCCAUGAAUAGUAUUUAAAUUGAUCCAAUCAUUAAGUGUGCAUCACUUCUCCUGUUCUGCCAAGACUUCUUCCUUUUUGCUUGCAUUUAAUGGACAUAGUCUUAGAAACAUUACAGAAUAAAAAAACCCAGACAUCUUCAGUUAUUUGGUGAUUAAAUGUACAUUAGCAAAUCUAUGUCUUGUCCUGAUUCACUGUCAUAAAGCAUGAGCAGAGGCUAGACGUAUCAUCCGGAUUGUUGUGAAACGUUUAAAAGCAGUGGUCCCUCCCUGCUUUUAUUCAUUUCCCCCAUCCUGGUUUAAGUAUAAAGCACUGUGAAUGAAGGUAGUUGUCAGGUUAGCUGCAAGGGUGUGGGUGUUUUUCUUUAUUUUAUUUUUUUGAGGGGGGUAAGUAGUUUUAUUUUAAUUUUAUGGGCUCCUUUCCCCGCCUUUUUGGUGAUCUAAUUGGAUUGGUUAAAAGCAGCUAACCAGUUCUUUAGAAAUAUGCUCUCUAUCCAAGUCUAACUUUAUUUAGACACUGUAGAUGGACAAGCUUGAUUGUUUGAACCAAAAUGGGAACAUUUAACAAGCAUCACUGCCCUCACUAAUAACAUUGUGACUUUGCUGUCAAGUGUAGAGUCCCCCCUUCAAAAUAAGCUUGUGACCAUUUUGUAUGGCUUGUCUGGAAACUUCUGUAAAUCUUAUGUUUUACUAAAAUAUUUUUUGUUAUUGUAAAAAAA